AGUGGCCGCAGCGCCUCCCGUGAGAGCGGUUUCUCCUCCUUGUACUGCUGGACCUGGCCCCGUAUCUUCGUGGCAGAGGCCAAGCAAGGGGACUCCGAUGCCGGGGCGUAGGGGGGUUUGGGUCAAAGGAUGGGGGCAGAGUUCAAAGUGCAGGGGGCGGGCUCGUUUAAUGGCGAAGUCCUGGCACCGCGCCCCAGGGAGGAGGCUCCGGAGGCCAGUGGAACCCCGCUAGACUUCAGGGGUCUUGGUUGGGGACGCGGGGCGUUUUGACCCCCUAGGCCUGAGGAUCCUAGGCCUGAGUAACCCAUCGGAUUUGGAGGGAAGGGUGGGGUUUAGGUGAAAUGUAAAUACUGCGUGGUUUCCAUUUGGCAAAGAGCAAGCUUGUAAAGGGGUCACCCUCGGGUCUGGGCUGCGAAGUGCAGCCGGGACCUGUUUCCUUGGGAACCACAAGAUAAGACCGCUGUAGAUUGUUAUGUCCGGAAACCGCUUAUCAGAGCCCUGCACCUGGGUUGGAAAUGGAGACGGAUUCUCUGUGUCCAAGAAAAUCAGACCCUCCGGCCGGAAAAGGGAAGUUUAUUCUUACUGAUAAAAUGUCAAUCACUGUGUAUGAUUGUAAUGGGCAAGGAAGGCAUUUAGCGAGCUAGAAGACAUUGAUGGCUCAGAAAAAGGUGUCCUUGGCAAAAAUACUGUUUUCUGUUAAUUUUCCAACUGAUACCAUCUGGGUCUGUCCUCCCAGCCUGAUGAAUGUGUAGGCAGAUACUUUCUCAGUCGGAGUUGAUUUUUAUUAUCUUGAUUGCUGCAUCCUGUGCACAGAGGUUUUCUGCUCAGCUGGGCUUCAUCCUGGGGUCCCAGUCCUGGCCCCAAGCCUUAAUCAGCUCUCGGGUGAUAUUAGGCAAGUUGCCAAGCCCCUAAGUGCCUCAGUUUCCAGGUCUGUAAAAUACAUAACAUUACCUGCAUUUGUCAAAUAGUGCUGUGUGUGGAUUAUUAUUGGCAGCUCAUCAUCACCAUUAUCACCCUCCUGUAAACGUCUUGGACCCCUUAAGUGAAGACAGCAGGGUUACGGCGGAUAAAAUGAUGGACUUCAGAGAAAAGACUCUAAGACCAAAUAGAGUCUAAAGCAGUGAUUAUCAAAGAGGGGAGGAGAAAUUUUACGCCCAGGGGACACUGGACAAUGUCUGCAGACUUGGUUGUCACAACCGGGGAUGGGGUUGGGGCGACUGGCAUCCAGUGGAUGAGGAGGUCUAGGGUGCUGCUCAACACCCUGCAAUGAAUAGCACGCCAGUCUUUUGGAUUUGAGCCCACCUUAAUCUCAUUUUAAUCGAAUUGCCUCUUUAAAGGCCUAUCUUCAAAUACCUUCUGAGGUACUGUGGGUUAGGCCUUCACCUUACGGAUUUGUGGGGACGCAAUUCACCCGUUAACGCUAUACAUACACAAAAAUUCAUAGACUACACCUCAAAAGAAAAAUUCAACAUGACCAUAUAAUACUAUAAAAUAAAAGAAGAUGCAAUACCUGGUUUGGGGUUGGAUCUUCGGAGGACCAGCUGUAAAGACCAUUUGGGGUAUAAUUGAAGGAAAUACGAUUAUGGGCUAGGUAUAAAGGAAUGAUUGUUAACUAUCUAAAGUGCGAAUAUGAAGUGUGGACUUUUAGAUAAAAAUACAGAUUUUUCUCUAAAAUAGCAUUUGGGAGGUGUUUAAGAGCAGAGUGUUACAGUGUCCUCAAUUUACUUUUUUUUUUUUUUUUGAGACGGAGUCUCGAGCUGUCGCCCAGGCUGGAGUGCAGUGGUGUGAUCUCGGCUCACUGCAGCCUCCACCUCCCGGGUUCAAGUGAUUCUCCUGCCUCACCCUCCCGAGUAGCUGGGACUACAGGUGCCCGCCACCACACCCAGCUAAUUUUUGUAUUUUUAGUAGAGAUGGGGUUUCACCAUCUUGGCCAGGCUACUCUUGAACUCCUGACCUCGUGACCCGCCUGCCUCGGCCUCCCAAAGUGCUGGGAUUACAGGCGUAAGCCACUGCCCCCAGCCACUCAAUUGACUUUGAAAUAAUUCUUUUUUUUUUUUUUUUUUUGAGACAGAGUUUUGCUCUGUUGCCCAGGAUAGAGUACAAUGGCGUGAUCUCAGCUCAACGCAAGCUCCGCCUCCUGGGUUCACGCCAUUCUCCUGCCUCAGCCUUCCGAGUAGCUGGGACUACAGGCACUCGCCACCACGCCCAGCUGAUUUUUUGUAUUUUUAGUAGAGACGGGGUUUCACCAUGUUAGCCAGGAUGGUCUUGAUCUCCUGACCUUGUGAUCCGCCCAACUCGGCCUCCCAAAGUGCUGGGAUUACAGACGUGAGCCACCGCACCCUGCGACUUUGAAAUAAUUCUAUGUAGAUAUUGGCUGUCAGUCGGCUAGAACAAUUGAUCAGGAAACAUCUCUGUCUUCACAAAUUACCUGAUAUGUUGAGUAAUGUGAGUAUAACACGAAUUUCAUAUUUGUUUAUGUUCAGUUUCAACCCUAAGAAACACUAAGUGAACAGAAGAAAUUGCACAUAACUGAAGAGUCUGGUAGGAAAACAGAAAAUGCGCGCACACACCUCAAAUACCAAGUCACACUGUUUCCUCUGCUUUAAAACUUAACAUUAGAUUUCCGACAACCCUCUCUCCACCACUGCAUACUAACUCUGGAAAUUUAGAUUCCCUUGCCCAAUUCCACAAGCAACCUUUGGAUCUUCUGCAAGGUACGUUGCUACAUUUAUUAUAGUAUUUAUGUGUUUCUUUUCCUUUUUUUUUUUUUUUUUUUGAGACAGAGUUUUGAUCUUGUUGCCCAGGCUGGAGUGCAGUGGCAUGAUCUCGGCUCACUGCAACCUCCACCUCCUGGGUUCAAGUGAUUCUCCUGCCUCAGCCUCCCGAUUAGCGGGGGUUCCAGGCAUUUGCCACCAUGUCCAGCUCAUUUUUGUAUUUUUAGUAGAGAUGGGGUUUCUCCAUGUUUGUCAGGGUGGUCUCGGACUUUGGACCUCAGGUGAUCUGCCCACCUUGGCAUCCCAAAGUGCUGGGAUUACAGGCGUGAGCCACCGCGCCCGGCCUAUUUAUGUGUUUCUUAAUGAUGUAAGGUGAAAAGCUGUGCUACUGUUUACUUCUUCAGGGACUCUGAUAAUAGGCAUGUUUUUCUUUCCUGUCUUUUGUUCCCACUGCUUCCUCUCUGACAGUUAUUCCACUGUUUCCUAUCACUUCCAAUUUCUUUGUAGUUUCCUUGCCUCUUAUCUUUGACACAAUGUGAGUAUCCUAAGCUUCAUUAAUAUCCAUUGAUGAAGGCUGAGGCAAGCGGAUCACUUGAGGUCAGGAGUUCCAGACCAACUUGGCCAGCAUGGUGAAACCCCAUCUCUACCAAAAAAUACAAAAAUCUGCCAGGCAUGGUGGUGCAACAUAAGACAAGCUUUGAGUAGCAAAAGAUUGGAAACAAGUCCACUGUCUAUUUAGAGAGACCUUGUUACAUCAGCUUACAUCAUCUUACAUCUGUAAGGAGUAAGGAAGUCACCUAUUAAGAUGAAGAGAGGUGGAGGAUUUAUUUUUUUCAUUGAGCCACAAAAACAAUUGUAAUGCAAUGUGUACACCAUGGUACUUUUUAAAAAUAAUAAAGCGGGGGGAAACAAAACGUGUCGUUCAAAUGGCGUUUUUUUGUUUGUUUUUGUUUUGAGAUGGAGUCUCGCUCUGUCACCCAGGCGGAGUGCAGUGGUGCGAUCUUGGGUCUGCAAUCCCCGCCUCCCGGGCUCUAGUGAUUCUCCUGCCUCAGCCUCCCAAGUAGUUGGGAUUACAGGCAUGUGCCACCACGCCCGGCUAAUUUUUAUAUUUUUAGUAGAGACAAGGGUUUUGCCAUGUUGGCCAGGCUGGUCUCGAACUCUUGACCUCAGGUGAUCCACCUGCCUCAGCCUCCCAAAGUGCUGGGAUUAUAGGCGUGAGCCACUGCGCCCGGCCCUAGAGAAUUUCUUAAAGUAAAAGGCUGUACUGUUCCUAUGGUAAUUGAAUUCUUAUUUUAACUCAUUUGAGAAAAUAAUCAUAGAAGUUUAAAUAAAUUUGAACUCGACGUGAAAAUUCUGAAUACUUUUAUUCAGUUGAGCCGCAAUUCCUAAAGCCUGGAACGCGACUGCUCAUCUCCGAAAAGACUUUCCAGCUUGAGACAGAGUAGAAGUAUAAACUCUAUAUCGCUUGCCAUUUUACAUACAAACAUAAUUGUCGUAAUUCAUGUUUUUACUGUGUCGACCUAAAUAACAGGCUGUCUAAAAACGGUGGUAACAGUUCAUUGCAGUGGGAAUAUGCGCGGCAUAGCAAACUAUGUGCUUAUUCAGGGAGGUAAAGGAAGACAAAGGUUGUUUUUGGUUUUCAUUUUUUUGAGACGGGGGUCUCUGUUGCCCAGGCUGGAGUACAAUGGUGAGAUCACAGCUCACUGCAGCCUCAAUCCCCACGGGCUCGAGCGAUCCUCCUGCUUCAGCCUAUCAAGUCGUUGGGACCAUAGGCGCACACUCCUUUAUUCCCAGCUAAUUUUUGUAUUUUUUGUAUAUAUGGGGUUUUGCCAUGUUGCCCAGACUGGGACAAAGGUUUAUAAAGGAAAAAAAAAAUUUUAAAUGAGGAUUACAUCAUUUUUCAGAAAUAAUUAUCCUUGUCUACAAAGAUCAGUAACAAGGGUCACACCAGUCUGAGUGUCCCUGUAAAAGUAUUUUUUGUUUAAGCCUGUGGUUUUUGUAGAGUCUUUUUCGUUAUUAAGCAUAUAAAUGUGAGACCUCUCUCUUCAUGACCUUACGUGGUUCUGUUUGUGGGAGGGCUGCUUUUUUUUUUUUUGAGACUCAGUUUCGCUCUUGUUGCCCAGGCUGGAGUGCAGUGUCCUGAUCUUGGCUCACUGCAAUCUCCGCCUCCUGGGUUCAAGCGAUUCUCCUGCCUCAGCCUCCGGAGUAGCUGGGAUUACAGGCGCCCGCCACCGUGCCCAGCUAAUUUUUGUAUUUUUAGGAGAGAAGUGGUUUUCGCCAUUUUGGUCAGGCUGGACUUGAACUCCUGACCUCUGAUGAUCCGCCGGUCUCCGCCUCUCACGGUGCUGGGAUUACCGGCGUGAACCACCGCGCCCGGCCGAGAGUUUUAAGAACACAGGGAGCGCCUGGUGGGGUCCGGCCUCCUGGGGCCUCGUCGUCUGGUCUCCAGAUCUCCAGGUCUCUGGACCCCAGGCGUCCGCGCCCACGCGGGACAGCACGGUGACGUCACGCACGCGGGUCCCGCCCCCACGCAGGACUCCGCCCCAUGGGACUCCGUGCCCUUCCUCUCCUCCCCGCACGAGGGGCCGCUCCGAGGGGAAACUGAGUCUGGAGUUGCCGUGCAGUCAGGGAGGAGGACGCCGCGCCCUCCCUGGACUGGAGUGAGUUCUCCCAGAUCCGCGGCUGCCCGGCUAGAGGGUCAGCCACGCGUGUUCUCGACGAGCCCGUCACUGAGGAGAGAAUUAUCCAAUCAGGACAGGCAGGGGCGGGGCCUAGGGAACUGUCCAAUCAGAGACGUUAAUCCGAAGCGGAGCCCUGCCCAAUCAAGGGCGCUAGGGGGACGGACUGGAGAAUUCUCCAAUCAGGGGUGCGGAGUCGACAGCACUGUCCAAUCAGAGUCUCCACUUCCCGAGAUCUGUCCAAUCAGACCCCGAGGACGGACUGCGUGAUCUUUGAGGAAGUGGCUGUGAACUUCACCCCAGAAGAGUGGGCAUUGCUGGAUCAUGCUCAGAGGAGCCUCUACAGAGAUGUGAUGCUGGAGACCUGCAGGAACCUUGCCUCCUUGGAUUGUUACAUUUAUGUUAGAACCAGUGGAUCAAGUUCUCAGAGGGACGUUUUUGGGAAUGGAAUAUCCAAUGAUGAAGAGAUUGUAAAGUUCACAGGAAGUGAUUCCUGGUCUAUUUUUGGAGAAAAUUGGAGAUUUGAUAACACUGGAGAUCAGCACCAAAUCCCACAGAGGCAUCUGAGAAGUCAGCUGGGGAGACUCUGUGAAAGUAAUGAAGGUCAUCAAUGCGGAGAGACCUUGAGCCAGACUGCGAACCUUCUUGUGCACAAGAGUUACCCUACCGAAGCUAAACCCUCUGAGUGCACUAAGUGUGGCAAAGCCUUCGAGAAUCGGCAGAGAUCUCACACUGGACAGAGACCGUGUAAGGAAUGUGGGCAAGCCUGCAGCUGCCUCUCCUGCCAAAGCCCUCCUAUGAAAACGCAGACUGUAGAGAAACCCUGUAAUUGCCAGGACUCAAGGACAGCAUCUGUGACAUACGUGAAAAGUCUCAGCAGUAAAAAGUCUUAUGAAUGUCAGAAAUGUGGAAAAGCUUUCAUUUGUCCCUCAUCUUUCAGGGGACAUGUGAAUAGUCAUCAUGGGCAGAAAACCCAUGCAUGUAAAGUAUGUGGGAAGACCUUUAUGUAUUACUCCUACCUUACACGGCACGUAAGAACUCACACAGGAGAGAAACCCUAUGAGUGUAAGGAGUGUGGGAAAGCCUUCAGCUGUCCCUCAUACUUUCGAGAACAUGUCAGAACACACACUGGAGAGAAACCGUAUGAAUGUAAGCAUUGUGGAAAAUCAUUCAGCUGUUACUCCUCCUUUAGAGAUCACGUGAGGACGCACACUGGAGAGAAACCCUGUCAGUGUAAACAUUGCGGAAAAGCGUUCACUUGUUACUCGUCUCUUCGAGAACAUGGGAGAACGCACAGUGGAGAGAAACCCUAUGAAUGUAAGGAAUGCGGCAAAGCCUUCAGGUACCCCUCCUCUCUGCGAGCACACAUGAGAAUGCACACCGGAGAGAAGCCCUAUGUGUGCAAGCAGUGUGGGAAGGCCUUCGGAUGUCCCACUUACUUUAGAAGACAUGUGAAAACACACAGCGGGGUGAAGCCCUAUCAAUGUAAAGAGUGUGGGAAAGCCUACAGUUUUUCCUCCUCCCUUCGAAUCCACGUGAGGACGCAUACUGGAGAGAAGCCCUUUGAGUGUAAGCAUUGUGGGAAAGCCUUCAGCUGUCACUCCUCCCUUCGAGAGCAUGUGCGAACCCACAGCGGAGAGAAACCGUACGAAUGUAAUCAAUGUGGGAAAGCCUUCAGCCACGCUCAGUACUUUCAAAAGCAUGUGAGAUCACACAGUGGGGUCAAACCCUACGAAUGUACUGAAUGUGGGAAAGCCUACAGUUGUUCCUCGUCCCUUCGUGUGCACGUGAGAACGCACACUGGAGAGAGACCGUAUGAAUGCAAGCAGUGUGGGAAAACCUUCAGGUAUCUCGCAUCGCUUCAAGCACAUGUGAGAACACAUGCUGGAGCGUGAAUCUACGAAUACAGUGGACCUGGGAGAGUGUUCAACCGUAAAACCUUGUUGUAAAUGUGAGAAACGUUAUUUAUGUAGAGCAUGUAGGAAAACCUGGUAUAGCACUUAUUUUGUACCUAAAAAUUCAGAGUAGGAGAGAAAUCUCUUAAUUAUGAUUAAUAUGGUAUUGCCUUUACAUGCCUCAGCCUUAAUAGUGAUUCCUUUUGUAUUAAUUUCUAGUGUAUGUUUGUGAUAUAAACAUUUAAUAAAUAUCCUGUUUUGUACGCUUUCA